GGAGUGGGGAGGCGGCAAGAGGACCUGCGGCAGGCCCUCUUCGGCAGUCUCUCCGGCCCGGUUUCCCUCGGCGUGCUACUGUGCGCUCGAUCCAGCACCAUGGGGAAGCGGGACAAUCGGGUGGUACUGCCAAAAUUAUGACAUGAUACCAAGGAAAUUAGAAUGUGAUCAAUAUUGUUGAAAACAAAAACAAAAACCUGAGACCAGUUAAAUUUAACAAAGGCCUAUAUGAACCCAAUAGCAAUGGCGAGAUCAAGGGGUCCAAUCCAGUCUUCAGGGCCAACAAUACAGGAUUAUCUGAAUCGACCAAGGCCUACCUGGGAAGAAGUAAAAGAGCAACUAGAAAAGAAAAAGAAAGGCUCCAAGGCUUUGGCUGAAUUUGAAGAAAAAAUGAAUGAGAACUGGAAGAAAGAACUGGAAAAACACAGGGAGAAAUUGUUAAGUGGAAGUGAGAGCUCAUCCAAAAAAAGACAGAGAAAGAAAAAAGAAAAGAAGAAAUCUGGUAGGUAUUCAUCUUCUUCUUCAUCAAGCUCUGAUUCUUCCAGCAGUUCUUCUGAUUCUGAAGAUGAGGAUAAGAAACAAGGAAAACGGAGAAAGAAAAAGAAGAACCGUUCACAUAAAUCUUCUGAAAGCUCCAUGUCAGAAACUGAAUCAGACAGUAAGGAUAGUUUAAAAAAGAAAAAGAAGUCAAAAGAUGGAACUGAGAAAGAAAAGGAUAUUAAAGGACUCAGCAAAAAGAGAAAGAUGUAUUCUGAAGAUAAACCUUUAUCAUCUGAGUCCUUGUCAGAAUCAGAGUAUAUUGAGGAGGUGCGAGCAAAAAAGAAGAAAAGCAGUGAAGAACGAGAAAAAGCAACAGAAAAAACAAAAAAGAAAAAGAAGCAUAAGAAACACAGUAAGAAGAAGAAAAAGAAGGCUGCUAGUUCAAGUCCUGACUCACCAUAACAUUAAGAAAAAUCAGGAUUCCCUUAUAAAGAAAGUGCAAUGUCUGAGGAAAUUUCAACUGUGAAAACUACAACAUAUUUACUAAAAUGCAUGAAUUUUCUUGUUUUUGGAAUUAUUCCUGGACUAUUCAGUAGCCACUCAGAUGCCACUGUGUGAAAGGGCCAUAAAUGUUGCCUGCUGCUUGAACAUCUAUUUUUUUCUCUUCCAGUGCUUGAUAACUCUGGGAGAUAAUACACUGCAGUCGUACUAGUGGUUAAGAUAUUUGGGAAUAAAAUUAAUACUUUUGACUAGAAGCGUCUAAGGAUAAACCAACAGAAAUUGAAUCUGGAUACAUCUUUAAGAUGUAAUCAGAAAUGACCAGAUGACUCUAGUUAGAAUUUUUGAAGGAGGGAUUACAUUAAUAUUUCAAAACCCUUACUCUGUAGAUAAGUGUAUUUUAAUUUUUUCCCCUCGUAUACUUUUAUUUACCUGGGGAAGGAGCUUUUAGGGUUGGGGGGUGGUUUGCUAUCUCUUUAGCUAGCAGAAUAGUGUGCCUUUGAUCCUCACACAUCCUGUAUUAUGGACACAGUAGCCAUGCUUCACGGGGAGGUCAGAGCUGGCUACCAGCAGUCUUGCCCUUUACUGAGCUUAGUGUCAUCUUUGGAUGCUGUCAUAUGCUGCUUUGAGUGAACCAGAGAAACAGCCAUUUGCAGCAUGAGAAAGCCCCAAAAGCUCUGGGAUUUACCUCCACUUUAGUAAUAAUGAAUAUUUUUUAGCAUUAGAAUGUGUUAUGUCAUUUGAAUUAAUUUUGACUACACUUUGGCUUGGGAGAGGAAUUAUUUUAAAUAGACAUUGGUACUUUUUGAACUUGAUAGCUAAAGAUUCUAAAAUGCAUGUUUUAUACUAAGUUUUAACCAGUCAGGAAAAUUUUAUGUAACUAGUGAUAGUUUAUUUUUUUGUAUGAAUUUUGUUUAGGCUGCAAUGUUUAGCUUUUGUUAACUCCUCACUCUUGCUGUCUUAAGUUCAUUACUAUGUUUAAUGGCCUACUUGCCAAGAUAUUUAGCAUGUAAAAAGCAGGGUUUUGAUUAAAAAAAAAAAACGGCUUCAUAUUGAAGCUGAGACUUACAAUAACAAGUUGAGUGGCAAGCCUGGUAUGCUGUGUCUUAUUGCCAGAAUCUUAGUAAAUGUAAUGUUUUAAAAGUUUGUUGUCUUUGUAUAUUAAUAACAAAUUAUGACAAGUUAAGUUUAAAUAAGAGUUACAUUAUUGCUCUCCCUGUGUCAUAUUUUACUAAGAUUUUGUGCCUCAUGUCUACUGCUGAAUUGUUUACUAGGAAUGUUAAAAGGAAUUGAUAAUUCAUUUUCAUUUUACAUUUUUAUAUAAUCAGGUAACAUGACAUACAACUUGAUGUACAAUUUUGCCUGUUACAAAGGGUGUGCUAAUUAUAGUGGUAUAUGCACAGAACAUGUUGGCAUGACAACAGGCUGAAUAAAUAGCUAUUUUACUUAAAAAUAGCUGUGUUCUUAUCAGCUCCCUUUGGACUGCAA